GCGUGGGGGUCUGUGGCUGCUGGGCUGGCGGGGCGCAGGCCGCGGGACCCGAGCCCGGGGAAGCGAGAGAGCGGAGGCGCCGAGGAUCCGAUUCACUCCCUGGGGAGACCUAUGGGCCGAAGCCGUGUAAAUGCGUUUUAAGAGGCCUCGGCUCCGCAACUGCCACUCCUCCUCGGGGUGUUGCACAAGUUUCGAGGUCACCGGCGACCCCCCCUAGCAGCGCGCCUGGCUCUGGCCCCCGCGAAGGAGGACGGAGUUUGUGUGUUGCAUACUUUCUAAGGCGGCGGCUGCAGCAGCGGCUCCAUCCAGCCCGUCAGCUCCUCCUGCAAGGCAUGGCUGGCUACCUGAGUGAAUCGGACUUUGUGAUGGUGGAGGAGGGCUUCAGUACCCGAGACCUGCUGAAGGAACUCACUCUGGGGGCCUCACAGGCCACCACGGACGAGGUAGCUGCCUUCUUCGUGGCUGACCUGGGUGCCAUAGUGAGGAAGCACUUUUGCUUUCUGAAGUGCCUGCCACGAGUCCGGCCCUUUUAUGCUGUCAAGUGCAACAGCAGCCCAGGUGUGCUGAAGGUUCUGGCCCAGCUGGGGCUGGGCUUUAGCUGUGCCAACAAGGCAGAGAUGGAGUUGGUCCAGCAUAUUGGAAUCCCUGCCAGUAAGAUCAUCUGCGCCAACCCCUGUAAGCAAAUUGCACAGAUCAAAUAUGCUGCCAAGCAUGGGAUCCAGCUGCUGAGCUUUGACAAUGAGAUGGAGCUGGCAAAGGUGGUAAAGAGCCACCCCAGUGCCAAGAUGGUUCUGUGCAUUGCUACCGAUGACUCCCACUCCCUGAGCUGCCUGAGCCUAAAGUUUGGAGUGUCACUGAAAUCCUGCAGACACCUGCUUGAAAAUGCGAAGAAGCACCAUGUGGAGGUGGUGGGUGUGAGUUUUCACAUUGGCAGUGGCUGUCCUGACCCUCAGGCCUAUGCUCAGUCCAUCGCAGACGCCCGGCUCGUGUUUGAAAUGGGCACCGAGCUGGGUCACAAGAUGCACGUUCUGGACCUUGGUGGUGGCUUCCCUGGCACAGAAGGGGCCAAAGUGAGAUUUGAAGAGAUUGCUUCCGUGAUCAACUCAGCCUUGGACCUGUACUUCCCAGAGGGCUGUGGCGUGGACAUCUUUGCUGAGCUGGGGCGCUACUACGUGACCUCGGCCUUCACUGUGGCAGUCAGCAUCAUUGCCAAGAAGGAGGUUCUGCUAGACCAGCCUGGCAGGGAGGAGGAAAAUGGUUCCACCUCCAAGACCAUCGUGUACCACCUUGAUGAGGGCGUGUAUGGGAUCUUCAACUCAGUCCUGUUUGACAACAUCUGCCCUACCCCCAUCCUGCAGAAGGACCCUCUGGCUAAGGAGCAAGGACUGGUGUUUAUAGACAGGAUCAGGGAGGUAAGCAUGAACUUUCAUGGUUUUCUCUGCCCCCAAGGGCACUGUGAGGCUCAGGAAGGGUGAAGUAGUGAAGGGCACAGGUUUGGUGCCUGACAGUCUGCGUAAGGACUCUAGCUCUGGGUCUCUAGCUAUGGCAACGUCAGUUGCCUAAGAGCUGUGAACCUUAGUUUUCUUAUCUGUGAAAGGAGUAACAAAAACUGCAUUGUAGGAUUGUGGUGAAGAUGAAAUGAGGGGGUGUUGUUGUGCGCACUCCAAGGCGCAGAGAAAGAGCCUGGUUAUUGAAGACUGCAAUUCUAAUAAGCGUUUCCCGGAAGUCUUCAUUGAGAGACGGGUUCUGAGCCGGGGCCUGAGGGAUGGGCAGGAUGUCAGUUGGGGGUCAGGGGAACAGGCAGAGGGAGCCGCAUGAGGAAGGGCUUAACGUCAGGACGACACGGGCUAUAGAAGUGCGGCCAGGCUGCAGCAGCAUGUGGGGCCUGCCUCUGCAAUUUUACUUUGUGGGAUUCUGGCUGGGAGUUCAUGGAGUCAGAAACCCCACUGUGUUCAGUGCCCAGGGCUCUGUGGGAGGCUCUACAAAGGCUCAAUUAGGGCCUGUUCCCUCCCCGACGCGCGGCUGCUGGCCUGCAGGAAGAACUGCUGGCGGUGGGCCAGCCUCGCUGCGCAUGCCCACCCAGAACGCCAGGCAGACAAAGGGGGGCGGACGAGAGUCUGGGGAUGCACGGCCAGGCUGCCGUGGCCUUCCUGAGCCCCCUCACCCGGGGAGGGUGGAGGCCUCUGCAGCGGCAUGUUGCUGAUGGGGAAGAUGGGGUCCGUCGUCCCUGCACCACCUGGAGCUGCCCUCCACAGGCGCCCAGACUCCGCAGCUACUCCUCUGGCUCCUCCUAGACCACUCUGCAGCACUUAGCCCACUCGCCACCCUCUCCUAGUUGAAAGUUCUGCUUUGCCUCCCAUCUCUGUGACUGCUGCCUCUCUGCCUCCCAUGUUCCUCGGGGCUCAUCCAGGUCAGCGCCUUCCAUCCUCACCCUGAACACCUGCCCCCAUUUUCAACUUGAACUGCUUUAAGGAUGGUUCCCAAGUCCAUAUAGAUGGCCUUGCCUGUCUCCUGAGUGCCACACCCAUUUUUCCAACAGUCUCCCCAACACAUCCCUCUGGGGUCCCACAGGUCUUUCCAACUCACUUGGUCUACAAGUCAACUCUUGUCUUUGCCAGCAAACUCACUGUCAGAGUGAUCCUUCUAAAGUGCCAACUGAAUCACAGAUGAUCCUGAGUUUAGGAACCUUCUUUAGCUCCUUGACACAUAGUAAAAUGCUGAACUCUUUAGUCUGGCAUUCAAGGACCUUCUCAAUUUAACCCUAGCUUACCUCCCUAGCGCCACUGCAUUGCAACUCCACCUGCCUAGAAUGACCCUACCCAAACCCUGUAUUCAACUGGCAAACUCCUACUCAUCCUGCAAGACCUAGCUUGAAAGUGACCUCUUCAGAGAUAACUUUCCUCUCUUUCAGGCACUUGGAUGUUCCCAGAGCCUUUUGUCAACAGUCUUAAUACAUUGUCCCACAUUUUCUGUCUCCCUGGCUAGUAAGUGGGCCCCUGCUGGGUAGGAAUGACAUCUCCCUCGGCUCUGCACCCCUGUGCCCAUCCCAGAGCCUGGUACAAGGCUGGCAAUCAGGAGUUGCUUGAGGGGUGAAGGAGGGAAGAGUCUUGUCUGAGAUUGCUCCGUAGAGCUGGGUGCAGGCUCCAGCUUCUUUCCAGGCUGGGGUUUCAAUGUCUCAAGGACGAGAGAGGAUGGGAGGGAAAGGGGGGAAGGCAGGGACAGGGCAGCCAGCAGUGGAACAUCAGAGUGACAGCCACCCCUGGAGCCCCAAGUACAUUCCCGAUGAGUCCUACUGACCUACCUGGCUUGCUGACUACAAAGCCAUAGCUCUUGCAGGACACCCCAGGAGACAUCCCAGCUGCACUAUGCACUGGGCUCUGACAGGACUGGAUGGUAAGCUCCCAAGUUGCCAUUUUCUAGCUGUGGGACUUCAGGUUGGUCCCUCAACCUCUCUGUGCCUCAGUUGCCUCACUGAUAAGAUUGAGAUAACAACAGUUCCUACCUGGGACGAUUUUUUUUCUUUCCUGUUUUUUUGGUUUUUGUUUUUGUUGUUUUUUAUUUUUUUGAGAUGGAGUCUCACUCUUGUUGCCCAGGCUGGGGUGCAGUGGCUCGAUAUUGGCUCACUACAACCUCCACCUCCUGGGUUCAAGCAAUUCUCCUGCCUCAGCCUCUUGAGUAGCUGGGAUUACAGGCACCCACCACCAUGCCCAGCUAGUUUUUGUAUUUUUAGUAGAGACGGGGUUUCACCAUAUUGGCCAGGCUGGUCUUGAACUCCUGACCUCAGGUGAUCCGCCCGCCUCAGCCUCCCAAAGUGCUAGGAUUACAGGCGUGAGCCACUGUGCCUGGCCGAUUUUUUUUUCCUUUCAAUCACUUUUUUUAUAACUACUUAUUGUGUGCCAGACACUGUGCUAGGUUUUAGGGAAUCCUGCUCUCGUGGAGGUGACAUUCUGUGAGGUUGGCAGGAUAAUGAAGAGGAACACAAUUCUCAGCACAGAGAAAAGUUCUGCUCAACUGGUGCACCCCAUUUAUUCUAGUUCUUUCCAGGGCAGAGUCACCCUUUCCCCAACCCCCUCCUUUCAGCUCUGUGGCUGGGGAAACAGCCCCCACCCCAACCCACCACAUCCCUUGGAACACCCUAGGGCCUGGAGGUGCUGGGGCCCUUUCAGAAAAACACCCUGCCAAGAAUGCAUCACCCCGCCAGGGCGCCGACCAAGGAAAACAGAGGGCCUGAGGAGGGAGAUCAGACAGGCCCUCAGGCCAGGCCAUUGGAGGGGCAGGCGCAGCAGGAAAGCCGAGUCAGGCACCAGGUGAAAUAUGACCUCCAAAGCAUCCAUAGGCAUUUCUUGUAUAAACACCCCAGUCCAGACAGGAAGUGGGGCUGGGGGAACUCGAGGGGGAUGUGGCCCCACAGGACCCCCCAGAGGCAGACAGAUGGACAGGAAAGCGGGGGAGGAAGAGGUCAGUGGAGAAAAACAAAGAGGGUGUGGGAUGUGGAGAGAAGAGAGUGCUGCUGGGGAGAAGGAACAGCCCAUAAUACUCCGCUCUCAUACAGAGAGAGGCUUCCAUUUGCUUCUCAUCAUCCAAGAGGUACAGAAUCACCAGACAGUUGGGGAAACUGAGGCUGCAAGAAGCAAUGAGGCCAGCAUCCUGUGACUGUUUAUCAUCUGUUGCCCCCGAGGGUCCUGCCCAGAGGCACUCUGGAAUGUUCUGUGAAGAAUUGUUUGUCAUGACCUUCCUGAGACCCCACAGUGGGUUGGUGGCCAAGCUGGGGCAUAGAUCUGGGUUUCCAAUGGUGUCUUCAGGCCCCAGGAUGACCUCCAGAGGCCCAGCGCAUUCCUAAGGCUCUGCCGCAGCUCCUGCUGACAGAGCGGGGUCAGCCUGAAAUCACCCCAGGCCUCACGACACAGAGUCACUCUGUAUAGUGGGGACUCCACCCGGCACCUUCCAGUCCCAGAGUGCUGGACUGAGCCUGGCAGUCCCCACUGGACAGAUGGGAAGGCUGGGGACCCAGGAAAGCAUGCAAUUUACCCAAAGUCACACAGUGAGUUAGUGGUGGGAUCAGAACCCAUGUCCUUCUCAAGUCAGUGGAAAAGUCUGUUUGUUUGUUUGUUUGUUUGUUUCCCAAACCACGGUAGCCAGAGACUGCAGAGUUUGGCCCUACCUUUCAGAGUCUGUAUCCCAUGGCCUGAGCUUAAGGGGAGAUGAUACCAGGGCUGGGCCACCUCUGGAGGGCUUCGAGGGGACAUGCUCAGGAUUGACUCCUAGGCAAUGGGCUUAUUCAUUCAUUCAUUCAUUCAUUCAUUUUAGAGACAGGGUAUCACUCUGUCACCCAGGCUGGAGUGCAGUGGCAUGAUCAUGGCCUACUGCAGCCUCAAACUCCUGGGCUCAGGCAAUCUUCCCAUCUGUCUCAGUCUCCAGAGUAGCUGGGACUACAGGCAUGUGCCACUACGCCUGGCUAUAUUCAAUUUUUUUUUUUUUUUUUGUAGAGAAGGCAUCUCGUUAUAUUGGCCAGGCUGGUCUCAAACUCCUGGGCUCAAGCCAUCAUCUUGCCUCGGCCUCUGAAGAGACUGGGACUACAAGUGUGUGUCACAACACCAGGGUUGGGCGGUUUUAAUAAGGGGAGAGGAGAAAGAGACUGAGCACAUUCCCCAGCCCUUCAGGAGGCAGGGGGUUUCCGGAGGGUCCCGGGACCCGCCUCAACUUCCACCCAAAGUGGGAAGGGAGAAAUGGCCCCGUCCUUAACCGAGGGACCAGCCCACAUCCUUGCCGCCAGUCAUGAUGGGGUGGGUGCCGCCCCAUUGAACUUCACGGAUGCCCUACCCUCUUCCCCACCCUGCCCUUCUCACUCCAGGUUUGGCUCCUUGAAGCCAGGUUUCCACCGCACACCCGAGGCCCCGCCCCUCUUCCCCAGCUGGCCCCGCCCCUCGAAGCCCUGCCCUCAUCUCUGCCGGCCCCACCUCCGCGCCCCGGCCAGGCUCACCUUGGUCUCCGCCAGUUGUCGCUUGAGCAGCUGCAGCGCUUCGGUGUGUUCCCGCUCGCUGUCUUGAAGGGCCUGAAGUUGGUCCUUCAGCUCCCUCUGAAACACACACAGGGCCGGGAUGGGGGCAGGGGCCAUGCCUGGCCCAGGCAUUCAGCCCUGACCACUGCCAGGCGCUGGGGGUUAGCCUGGUCUCUGUCCCCAACCUCCAACACUUGCCUCCCGUCACAGUUCAACCACCAGCAAGUCCUGUAGAGUCUGUCUCCUAAACACCUCCAGAACCCGUCCGUAUCUUUCACCUGCAUCUUUGCAACAACCUCCUCCUCUUUGGCCACCCUAGAGGCUUCUGUGACAAUCGACUUCCACAUACACACUCUCUGGCUCCCCACACUUGGCCCUGGAUCCCCGCUUAGAAUUAAGGCAGGGGUCUCCAACCCCCAGGCCACAGGUGGGUAUUGGUCCAUAGCUUGUUAGGAACCUGGACGCACAGCAGGAGAUGAACAGUGGUGGGGAGGGGCAAACCAUCUGUAUUUGCAGCCGCUCCUCAUCGCUGGCAUUACCACCUGACUCCACCUCCUGUUGGAUCAGUGGUGGCAUUAGAUUCUCACAGGAGUGUGAACUGCACAUGGGAGGGAUCUAGGUUGCCUGCUCCUUAUGAGAAUCUAAUGCCUGAUGAUCACUCACUGUCUUCCAUCACCCCCAGAUGGGACUGUCUAGCUGCGGAAAAACAAGCUCAGGGCUCCCACUGAUCCUACAUCAUGUUGAGUUGUGUAAUUAUUCCAUUAUAUAUUACAAUGAAAUAAUAAUAGAAAUAAAGUGCACAAUAAAUGUAAUGUGCUUGAAUCAUCCUGAAACCAUCACCCCACCCCCACCCCCUGCGGUUUGUGGAAAAAUUGUCUUCCAUGAAGCUGGUCCCUGGUGCUAAAAAGGUUGGGGACCACUGCUCUAAGGAACCAAAGCUGUACCAGUCCAAUGCUACAGACUAGCUGCCAACAUUCUCCGAGGGCUACAGUGGGCUGGGCACAGUUCUUAGCUCUUUGCUUAUAUUAAAUCAUUUGGGCCUCUCAGUAACCCUAAGGGAGGCACAAUUAUUAUCUCCAUCUUCUGAUGGAGAAAAAGAUACAGAGAGGUCAAGAAACUGGCCCCAUAGCAUACAGAUAAACAUAUAAUGGUAAAGAAGGAAUUGGAACCCGGACAGCCUGGUUGUGGAGACCAUGAUCUUGAUGCCAGGUGACACGUUUUCUACCAUGAUGACUCCUGCGAUGAAUAACAACAAAUCCACAACACACAAGAUAUCAAAAUUUUAAAUAAAAACACAAUCAGCCUCA